AGUCCCCACCCCCCAGCCAGGUCUCAUAGAGGGAAUUGUUCUUCAGGCUCGGAGGGGCCUGCCUGUCACUGCGCCCCCGACCCUAGCUCAGGGACUGCAGAACUCAAGAUACCAUCCCGUUUCUCCUGGCUGAGGAAGGGAAGGGAACAUCCACAUCUUCUGUACUCGUCCAUUCUGUGUCCCCGGGGCCUGGAGUAAAGACACCUUCAAAUGCAGAGACUCUUCAGAUUCAGCUUUCCUGGAAACUGAUCUUCAAUGCACUAAGAGAAGGAGACUCUCAAACCAAAAAUGACCUGGAGGCACCAUGUCAGGCUUCUGUUUACGGUCAGUUUGGCAUUACAGAUCAUCAAUUUGGGAAACAGCUAUCAAAGAGAGAAACAUAACGGCGGUAGAGAGGAAGUCACCAAGGUUGCCACUCAGAAGCACCGACAGUCACCGCUCAACUGGACCUCCAGUCAUUUCGGAGAGGUGACUGGGAGCGCCGAGGGCUGGGGGCCGGAGGAGCCGCUCCCCUACUCCCGGGCUUUCGGAGAGGGUGCGUCCGCGCGGCCGCGCUGCUGCAGGAACGGCGGUACCUGCGUGCUGGGCAGCUUCUGCGUGUGCCCGGCCCACUUCACCGGCCGCUACUGCGAGCAUGACCAGAGGCGCAGUGAAUGCGGCGCCCUGGAGCACGGAGCCUGGACCCUCCGCGCCUGCCACCUCUGCAGGUGCAUCUUCGGGGCCCUGCACUGCCUCCCCCUCCAGACGCCUGACCGCUGUGACCCGAAAGACUUCCUGGCCUCCCACGCUCACGGGCCGAGCGCCGGGGGCGCGCCCAGCCUGCUACUCUUGCUGCCCUGCGCACUCCUGCACCGCCUCCUGCGCCCGGAUGCGCCCGCGCACCCUCGGUCCCUGGUCCCUUCCGUCCUCCAGCGGGAGCGGCGCCCCUGCGGAAGGCCGGGACUUGGGCAUCGCCUUUAAUUUUCUAUGUUGUAAAUAAUAGAUGUGUUUAGUUUACCGUAAGCUGAAGCACUGGGUGAAUAUUUUUAUUGGGUAAUAAAUAUUUUCAUGAAAGCGCCUUUGGCUCCAGAUCCUUGGGAGAGGGACACGUGUGUCCCCAGCACCACUGUGACCGGUAGGUAGAGACAGCAGAACAACAGCGAGAAGGAGCCAAAGCUGGAGCCAGAAAGCCUGGCACCGCCACCUUCCCCUGACAGUUAGCACCUUCCUUUCACAACAUCUCCCUUAAGGGGGAAGCGUCUGCUGUGGAACCCACCGCAAGGCAACGCAGGCAGAGUUCAGCCUGAAGAGCGCCAGGCCAGCCUCCUCUGUCUUCCGAGCACCGCUUCUCAGGUCGCUUCCCAAUCUGAGGAGGCUGUCGUGUCCACAACCAGUCCAGGGGGAUGUGCGCCACUAGCUGAGGACGCCAGGCCCGGCGACACCACAAAGGCUUGGCCAUGCGGAAUGUGCCCUCAAGAGCACACACUUCGGGUAGAGGGCACUUGCAUUGAGCUCUUCAGCUUUUUAAAUCCACUGUAGUUCAUGAGCCUGUGUGACAUAAUUACUUUUACAUUUUAUAUUGUCAAUUAGUUUAUUGGCAUUUUCAAUCUUUUCAACUAUUGGCUAUGAAAAUAUGAAUUUAACGUAACAUUCAAAUGAGUAUUAAAGAAAAAUAAAGUAGAACUUCAUUAGA